CUAGGGGACUGAGGUUGGGCCUGCUGCCCACGGCCUGCCCACUUUACCCAGAUGUCCAGCAAGGUGGCCAUCAACAGUGACAUUGGGCAGGCCCUCUGGGCAGUGGAGCAGCUCCAGAUGGAGGCAGGCAUCGACCAAGUGAAGGUGAGGGUCGGGGCCAGUGCAGGAGGCGGGAAGAGGUGGGAACACAUGGGCCAGGGGACAGGUGCAUGCCUGGGUCUGGUCUGGCUGAACCAGUUGGUCUGCAGGUGUCCAAAGAUGGCCGCCGAUCUGCUGAAGUUCUGCACGGAGCAGGCCAAGAAUGACCCCUUCCUUGUGGGCAUCCCGGCCGCCACCAACUCCUUCAAGGAGAAGAAGCCCUAUGCCAUCCUAUGAACCCAGGGCAAUGCCACCCUGUGGCCUGGGCAAACCAGGGGGCCUCAAUA